AAUUUCUCAUCUUUCUGUUCCCACUGCCCUUAAGAGUGAUUUGCAUAUUUAACUCAAUAAGCAUCUACUGAAAUGAGUUGAUCUGUUGAUGUAAGUCUGCUCAAUAUGGUCUUGCUCUCAGAAUAUGUUUCUUGCCUUUUUGAUGCUUUAGAAGGCUUUCAAGGUAAGUCAAGCAGGGAACCUGGUGGGUAGAUGAGGGAAUUUUCAAACACACAACUGUCUGAUUUAGGAUCCUACAUGGACUUGGUAUAUAGUGUCACUUACUUGUAAAUCAGAUUUUUAAAAUUGGAAGCAACUCUGUGAUCAUCUAGUCCAUCUAGUCUACACCCUUCCUUUUACAAAUGAAGAAUCCAAGAGCCAGAAGCUCCCAGACAUCCUGACUCAAUGUCCUAUAUUUGUUGUAUAGCCUCCUUUGUGGAAGUUAUGUAUGCAUUUGACUUCACUUAAUCUAAGACAUCUAUUUUCCUUGAACUCUUGAUAGGUCUGCUGGUUUCCUCAAGGGAAUCCAAUCUAGCUGGAUUUUAAUCUCUUUGAAUUGUGUCCUCAGCUAUAAAAGUUUUAGCUGAGGUUUUAAUGGCUGCACUUAAGUAAAUCUAACAGAUAUACCAGGGGGUGUUCCAAUUACAUACACCAUUAAAGGGCUUUAUGUGAGGAUUUUUAAAAAUUACCAUUAAAAAAAAAAAAGCAUAGUCCAUUUGCAGUAUAAUUUACCAGCAGGAAAGAUUUCAAUGUCCUGGAAAAAUUCCCUAUAAAAAGGAAGAUAGGAAAACAGAAAAGUCACAGUACUCAACCUACUUCAAGGGAAGAUUGGGAUCUUUUUGGCUCUCUGCCUCUAAACAGGUAAAAGGCUUUGUAUUAUUUCUAGCACGAGUUUUUCUUCUUUAGAUUGCAUGCUAUUGUAUGUCUACAGGGCAUUUGACAGCCCAAGGGCUAAAUCCAGGUGUGACGGUAUCUAAUGAUGUCCUGUCCUUCACUGUCCUUGCCAUCACCAGCCACAGAGAUCCAGGCUUUGGGGACUCCCACAGCUUAUCGACCAGUGUUUGAUUUAGUUUUUAGCCUCUUUCCCAUCAAAUGAAAAUUAACUUGGAGACACAUUUCAUUAGAAAAUUAGAGGCCCCCUUGGCUAGGAAGGCAUCUGGUCUGGGACUAACUACUUUGAACAGUGUUGAGUCCUCUCUCCCACAGAUGGUUCAGCCAGCAGUAAUGCUAGGAAGACUGAAGGAUAAAUAGAAAAAUGUCAUUAGUACCAUGGGGUAGCCAUGUAAUGUCAAGCAAUUUUAUAUUAGCCAGAGAUUCCUAGUAGGAGCUACUUUUCUUAACAGAUGACUCAGUUCUCUUUAUCUCAGGAAUGAAAGAGUUGAAGACCAAUCCACAACAGGGGAAAUGUUAAGGCAAAAUGAUGAACUUGAUAAGGGAUGAAUUAUGGGGUUUGGAUAACCAAACAAUAAAAAUAAAAGUAUAGACUAUUUUAGUACUAAAAAGGUCCUGAACAUGUGAGCUUAAGUACUCAUUUUGUCCCCAGUGGCUAAGAAACUAAAGGCAAGCCAGCAAGUGUCUCUGAGUUUCAGUGUCUGUAUGUAAAAACUGACUCUGACUUCCAUCUUCUGCAGGGUUAGUGAUACAGAUGCUAGCUUUUUCACUAAAGAGGUCUUUUAGUUUAUACUCAACCUUGUCUGGAUCUAAUUUGAUUGUGCAUUCAUGUGCCUUAGAAUGAAGCCAAUUCAAAAACUCCUAGCUGGCCUUAUUCUACUGACUUGGUGCGUGGAAGGCUGCUCCAGCCAGCACUGGUCCUAUGGACUGCGCCCUGGAGGAAAGAGAGAUGCCGAAAAUUUGAUUGAUUCUUUCCAAGAGAUAGUCAAAGAGGUUGGUCAACUGGCAGAAACCCAACGCUUCGAAUGCACCACGCACCAGCCACGUUCUCCCCUCCGAGACCUGAAAGGAGCUCUGGAAAGUCUGAUUGAAGAGGAAACUGGGCAGAAGAAGAUUUAAAUCCAUUGGGCCAGAAGGAAUGACCAUUACUAACAUGACUUAAGUAUAAUUCUGACAUUGAAAAUUUAUAACCCAUUAAAUACCUGUAAAUGGUAUGAAUUUCAGAAAUCCUUACACCAAGUUGCACAUAUUCCAUAAUAAAGUGCUGUGUUGUGAAUGAA